GUUUCUCCGGGCUACAGCCGGCGCCGCCGCCCGCUAGUCCGCCGCCCGGCGCCAUGGCGGGCUGCGCGGCGCGGGCUCCGCCGGGCUCUGAGGCGCGUCUCAGCCUCGCCACCUUCCUGCUGGGCGCCUCGGUGCUCGCGCUGCCGCUGCUCACGCGCGCCGGCCUGCAGGGCCGCACCGGGCUGGCGCUCUACGUGGCCGGGCUCAACGCGCUGCUGCUGCUGCUCUAUCGGCCGCCUCGCUACCAGAUAGCCAUCCGAGCUUGUUUCCUGGGGUUUGUGUUCGGCUGCGGCACGCUGCUAAGUUUUAGCCAGUCUUCUUGGAGUCACUUUGGCUGGUACAUGUGCUCCCUGUCAUUGUUCCACUAUUCUGAAUACUUGGUGACAGCAGUCAAUAAUCCCAAAAGUCUGUCCUUGGAUUCCUUUCUCCUGAAUCACAGCCUGGAGUAUACAGUAGCUGCUCUUUCUUCUUGGUUAGAGUUCACACUUGAAAAUAUCUUUUGGCCAGAACUGAAGCAGAUUACCUGGCUCAGUGUCACAGGGCUGCUGAUGGUGGUCUUCGGAGAAUGUCUGAGGAAGGCGGCCAUGUUUACAGCUGGCUCCAAUUUCAACCACGUGGUACAGAAUGAAAAAUCAGAUACACAUACUCUGGUGACCAGUGGAGUGUACGCUUGGUUUCGGCAUCCUUCUUACGUCGGGUGGUUUUACUGGAGUAUUGGAACUCAGGUGAUGCUGUGUAACCCCAUCUGCGGCGUCAGCUAUGCCCUGACAGUGUGGCGAUUCUUCCGCGAUCGAACAGAAGAAGAAGAAAUCUCACUAAUUCACUUUUUUGGAGAGGAGUACCUGGAGUAUAAGAAGAGGGUGCCCACGGGCCUGCCUUUCAUAAAGGGGGUCAAGGUGGACCUGUGACGGGCAGUGGCCCCGGUGACCUUGGGGCCUCCGACCCUGUGCAGCCUGGGACAAAACUGUUUCCGGUUGGCCGCUGCCACAUGGAUUUUCUUAAUCGUUUUAUGUCAUUAGUCACUCUUCUGGAAUGUCACUCAAGACCAAGCGGUCAGAAGGCCUGAGGACCCAAGGCCCCACUGGAGCAGUCUGUCCUUAUGCCGAAUCAAGGCGGAACAUGGGUGAAAGACGAGUAAGGGGCAAAUCACAGCAAUAUUCCACAGCGCCCUCCAGAGUUACCUGGGGAGGACCGAGGCCACACGCCACUGCCCCCGAGGCCAGAGUGUAAGUAAAGGAUAACCAGGACUCGCUGGGAGAGAUGGACUCUGUCCUCAGCAACACUCCACAGCAGAAAGGGGUAGCAGGUACCCCUUCUUAUCAGCGGUAAAAAUGCAUUUACAACCUUUCAUUUAACCGAAAAACACAGACCGCUUUAACCUCUUUAUUUCUGUCCCCCACUGCAUGAACAUCUAUACAAUUUUAAAAAUACUUCCUCAUAGGAUGCUUUGGCCCUUCAUCUAUUUAAUCAUAGCUACAUACCUAUUUUUUAUAAGUAGCAGUACACAUUCAAAGGGGUAUUCCUAGCUCAAUGCUUGGUGUUCUAGUUCAACUUUUAUCCUGCAGCAAGUAAGCCUAGAUAACUCUACACGAUUUGGCUGAGUGGCUUUGUGUGACCGUGGCCCCAGGCCAAGGGGAUCAUGGCCCUGGCUGGCUUUCCCGGGGGUCUCAGCUCCUGUUGUCAGUGAUAGGCGGCUCAAAGGAGCAUCAGUUUCUUUUGAUCCAAGAAGUGCUUACUGAAUGCCUGCCCUGUGCGUGGCCUUAAACAUUGAGAAGUGCUGCUCUCCGUUUAUUUGGGAUUUGAUUCUCAUUUUACCAUAGCUUAUAUUCUCAAUUUCAAUGCCAGUCUCAGAACUCUUGUUUUCUGUGUUCUGUUCUCAAAAUUACAUUGUCCCUCAUGUCAUUUCAAACUGUUUUCCAAAGGGAUUUGAGCAUAUACAACUACAAAUCCAAGCAGAUUGACUCUCAAAAAUAAUCUUAAAUACUGCAAAUAGUCCCAACUAAGAUUCAGUCAGUAUGUUUGUUUUGCAAGUUUGGGAGAGUAAGUUGGCUUUGAGUCACACAUCGAAGCUUUAAGAGGUGAGACGCUGGCUUCAUUCUGGACUAGACAGGAACUUGGCCUCAGCGUGAGAUCCUGCCAUGCAGUGUUGCGGUGGCACUGAAGAAGUGUGAAUGUGAAGGCGGCGUCGGCGCGGGGCCAGAGCACCACUCUGCUGCCCCACCACGCGGCCUGUGAGGAGCCACUAAACCUUUCCGUGCCUAGACCUCCCCAUCUGUGGAAUGGGGUCAAUACCACCUACCUCACAGGGGUGUUGUGAGGACUGAGAAGAACAAUGUCAAAUGUUUUUAAUACUCAGAUGUGGGAGCGACAUCAAUGAAAUCUGUACUGUAUGAAAGCUACACAAAAAUGGGCAGACAUUUGGUUAAUUGUGCCAGAUACCUAAAAUGUAUGUUCAGAAAAGCAUUUUAUCAACUCAGAAAUAUGACUUAUUUCUAGAUUUCAUGGCUUAAUGAAUUUUUUCAUUGUUAUAUAUACCAAAGAGGCUUACGGGUUCAUUGAUUGGUUUGAAAACCAGACAGACGGCCGGGCGCGGUGGCUCACGCCUGUAAUCCCAGCAAUUUGGGAGGCCAAGGCGGGUGGAUCAUGAGGUCAGGCGUUCGAGACCAGCCUGGCCAACAUGAUAAAACCCCGUCUCUACUAAAAAUACAAAAAAAUAGCUGGGCGUGCUGGCGGGUGCCUGUAAUCCCAGCUACUCAGGAGGCUGAGACAGGAGAAUCCUUUGAACCCAGGAGGCGGAGGUUGCAGUGAGUUGAGAUCGGGCCUUUGCACUUCAGUCUGGGCAACAGGGCGAGACUCCAUCUCAAAAAACAACAACAACAACAAAAAAAACCGGACGGACUUGCCCAUCGGCCCUCACGACACGCGUGCAGUGGGACUCUAGCCAAGGCGGUGGCCGAGCCAUCAUUACAAUUUUUCUGGAGUAAAGGAUCCACGGUGGGACAUCAACUGGCACUUACUCUGUUUAGGAACUUGAGUUGAAUCAUUUCUAAACUUGUCCUUUAGACCACGCCUAGGGCAGCAAAUUCCACUUCCUAGAACUGCAAACCGGGAGAGGAUGUAGUUAGAUUCUGGCAUCCUGCCCCGGCUCUUUGAGGGAAAAGUUCUUUCCCCUGCUCUAAGUAGGGCGGGCCCAGCCUCCAUUCCCAUUGGGAGCCAUGAAGUUGUCUUGUUGAUAGGUCUAGGGCAGCUGUUGGCAGCUGCUGGCCUUGUGGAUGGUAAGCUGACUGUGUUGGCAUUUAAUGCCAUCCUCCAUCUGCCAGAGGCCCAGGAAGCCCACCUUCACACCAGGCCCACCAGCUGGAAGGAGCCCAGGAGGCAGGUCUUAGGGUUUCAUGGUGAAAUGCUGUCUGACACCAGGGAAAACUUGACGUACUCUGCUUUGGAGAGGAAUUCCAGGGGUAGGGAUGGUGGGAGAACAUUCCCACCCUGUUUAUAAUCCCAGAGCAGAAGUCAGCAAUUACUUAGGGAUAAAAGAUGAACUCCAUUUUUUUUAUUUUCUUAAGACAGUCUUGCUCUGUGGCCCAGGCUGGAGGCUGGAGUGCAGUGGCACCAUUUCGGCUCACCGCAACCUCUGCCUCCCGGGUUCAAGCGAUUCUCCUGCCUCAGCCUCCUGAGUAGCUGGGAUUACAGGCUUGGGCCACCAUGCCCAGCUAAUUUUUUUGUAUUUUUAGUAGAGACGGGGUUUCACCAUGAUGGCCAGGCUGGUCUCGAACUCCUGACCUCAAGUGAUCCACGCGCCUCGGCCUCCCAAAGUGCUGGGAUUACAGGCGUGAGCCACCACGCCCAGCCAAGAUGAACUCCUUAAGGACAGGAUUUGGUAAGUGAUUGACUUCUUUUUAGUUCCAUGAUCUUGAGAUUAUUUUUAGCUUUAUAAAUUUAGCAGUGGCAGGGCCCGUGGAGAAUCAGGUUAAUGAGGUAAAGGCUUUCUGGGUAUUUGCUGCCAAGGCCACAUCACCAAUUUUCUCGAUUUAAAAAACUGUCAAGAGAUUUAUUUUUCCAUUGCAGGUUUUAAAGUGGAGAUUCUGAAGUGGAAAAUAGGUACUGUCAGAACAAAGCUACCUGGAAACAGCAUAGAGUGAAGCCUUUCGUGAGGGCUUGCAGGCCGCUGCUGAGUGGCAGUUUACAGAAGAGGUCGCGGGGUGAGCCUCUUAGCAGGACAGAAAACAAGGCAGCAGCGCACCUGCCACCCCUUCACGAGCUGCUCCUUGAGCCUAAAAAGUAGGCUUUAUUCAUCCCUUCUGUUCAUUUACCAACCUGGGGGAUUGAUACGACCGGGGAAAAUGUUCCUAAACCAGGAAGCUGCGUUAGCCGAUCAGGCUUUGUAAGAUCUCGCCAACAGCUAGCUGCUUAGGAGUACCCCCACGAUACGCACAGCACACCACUGUCCCUUCACUGCACUUUCUUCCUGCCUUAGGUAGUUGGGCUUGCCCACCCUAGUUUGCUUUUGUAGUGGUUUGGCAAGGUUAGAAGGCCUCGGCCUCUCUGUCAUGCUGGGAAGUGCCUACUCUCUGGGCCACUGCUGCAGAGGCCGUGGCACUUGUCAUGGGUUUGGAAGACCCAGCCAUCUGCAGCAGAGGCAGCCUAUCCCAUUGCAAGGAGAGGAACUGAACGGAGUAAUUAUUCUACUCUUCUUUUUACAUAAAUGUUUAUUUAAAUAUUCUAAAUUGGAUUUUCUUUCACAGAUACUGAUUAUUCUUUCCAGUUCUUAAAUAAAACUGCACUUGAUUUCACUCAA